GUUUCCGGCCGCCGUCGCUGUCCAGGGAGGCUGAGGCGAGAGGUAGCUGUCCGGGUGGGGAGCCCGCACUACCUUCUUCCUCUUCCUCCUCCUCCUCCGGGUGAGGGGAGCGAAGGUUGGGGGUCCCCGAGCCCAUGGACCAGGAGGAGGCGGAGGCCGCCGAGAGCCGGGGCCCCGCUAUGUGGCCCUGAGCCCCGUGUACUGGUUCUGCCUGUCUGGAGGGCCAUGGAGAAGAGGCUGGGAGUCAAGCCAAAUCCUGCUUCCUGGAUUUUAUCAGGAUAUUAUUGGCAGACAUCUGCGAAGUGGUUGAGAAGCCUGUACCUGUUUUAUACUUGCUUUUGCUUCAGCGUUCUGUGGUUGUCAACAGAUGCCAGUGAGAGCAGGUGCCAGCAGGGGAAGACACAAUUUGGAGUUGGCCUGAGAUCUGGGGGAGAAAAUCACCUCUGGCUUCUUGAAGGAACCCCCUCUCUCCAGUCAUGUUGGGCUGCCUGCUGCCAGGACUCUGCCUGCCAUGUCUUUUGGUGGCUAGAAGGGAUGUGCAUUCAGGCAGACUGCAGCAGGCCCCAGAGCUGCCGGGCUUUUAGGACACACUCCUCCAAUUCCAUGCUGGUGUUUUUAAAAAAAUUCCAAACUGCAGAUGAUUUGGGCUUUCUACCUGAAGAUGAUGUACCACAUCUUCUGGGGCUAGGUUGGAACUGGGCAUCUUGGAGGCAGAGCCCACCCAGAGCUGCACUCAGACCUGCUGUAUCUUCCAGUGACCAGCAGAGCUUAAUCAGGAAGCUUCAGAAGAGAGGUAGUCCCAGUGACGUAGUUACACCUAUAGUGACACAGCAUUCUAAAGUGAAUGACUCCAACGAAUUAGGUGGUCUGACUACCAGUGGCUCUGCAGAGGUCCACAAGGCGAUUACAAUUUCCAGUCCCCUAACCACAGACCUGACUGCAGAGCUGUCUGGUGGGCCAAAGAAUGUAUCAGUGCAACCUGAAAUAUCAGAGGGUCUUGCUACUACGCCCAGCACUCAACAAGUAAAAAGUUCUGAGAAAACCCAGAUUGCUGUCCCCCAGCCAGUGGCUCCCUCCUACAGUUAUGCUACCCCUACCCCCCAGGCCUCUUUCCAGAGCACCUCAGCACCAUACCCAGUUAUAAAGGAACUGGUGGUAUCUGCUGGAGAGAGUGUCCAGAUAACCCUGCCUAAGAAUGAAGUUCAAUUAAAUGCAUAUGUUCUCCAAGAACCACCUAAAGGAGAAACCUACACCUACGACUGGCAGCUGAUUACUCAUCCUAGAGACUACAGUGGAGAAAUGGAAGGGAAACAUUCCCAGAUCCUCAAACUAUCGAAGCUCACUCCAGGCCUGUAUGAAUUCAAAGUGAUUGUAGAGGGUCAAAAUGCCCAUGGGGAAGGCUAUGUGAACGUGACAGUCAAGCCAGAGCCCCGUAAGAAUCGGCCCCCCAUUGCUAUUGUGUCACCUCAGUUCCAGGAGAUCUCUUUGCCAACCACUUCUACAGUCAUUGAUGGCAGUCAAAGCACUGAUGAUGAUAAAAUCGUUCAGUACCAUUGGGAAGAACUUAAGGGGCCUCUAAGAGAAGAGAAGAUUUCUGAAGAUACAGCCAUAUUAAAACUAAGUAAACUCGUCCCUGGGAACUACACUUUCAGCUUGACUGUAGUAGACUCUGAUGGAGCUACCAACUCUACUACUGCAAACCUGACAGUGAACAAAGCUGUGGAUUACCCCCCUGUGGCCAACGCAGGCCCCAACCAAGUGAUCACCCUGCCCCAAAACUCCAUCACCCUCUUUGGGAACCAGAGCACUGAUGAUCAUGGCAUCACCAGCUAUGAGUGGUCACUCAGCCCAAGCAGCAAAGGGAAAGUGGUGGAGAUGCAGGGUGUUAGAACACCAACCUUACAGCUCUCUGCGAUGCAAGAAGGAGACUACACUUACCAGCUCACAGUGACUGACACAAUAGGACAGCAGGCCACUGCUCAAGUGACUGUUAUUGUGCAACCUGAAAACAAUAAGCCUCCUCAGGCAGAUGCAGGCCCAGAUAAAGAGCUGACCCUUCCUGUGGAUAGCACAACCCUGGAUGGCAGCAAGAGCUCAGAUGAUCAGAAAAUUAUCUCAUAUCUCUGGGAAAAAACACAGGGACCUGAUGGGGUGCAGCUCGAGAAUGCUAACAGCAGUGUUGCUACUGUGACUGGGCUGCAAGUGGGGACCUAUGUGUUCACCUUGACUGUCAAAGAUGAGAGGAACCUGCAAAGCCAGAGCUCUGUGAAUGUCAUUGUCAAAGAAGAAAUAAACAAACCACCUAUAGCCAAGAUAACUGGGAAUGUGGUGAUUACCCUACCCACGAGCACAGCAGAGCUGGAUGGCUCUAAGUCCUCAGAUGACAAGGGAAUAGUCAGCUACCUCUGGACUCGAGAUGAGGGGAGCCCAGCAGCAGGGGAGGUGUUAAAUCACUCUGACCAUCACCCUAUCCUUUUUCUUUCAAACCUGGUUGAGGGAACCUACACUUUUCACCUGAAAGUGACCGAUGCAAAGGGUGAGAGUGACACAGACCGGACCACUGUGGAGGUGAAACCUGAUCCCAGGAAAAACAACCUGGUGGAGAUCAUCUUGGAUAUCAACGUCAGUCAGCUAACUGAGAGGCUGAAGGGGAUGUUCAUCCGCCAGAUUGGGGUCCUCCUGGGGGUGCUGGAUUCCGACAUCAUUGUGCAAAAGAUUCAGCCGUACACGGAGCAGAGAAAGAUCAGUAGUGUGGAAGCUAGUCUAAAAUAGGGAGAGACCAAAGGCUGGGAGACCAUUCAGGAAGCUUCUGGACUAGUCCAGUGAAAAGGUAAUAAAACCUGAAUUAAGAUAGUGGAAGAAGAGGAGAAGAAAUUAAAAGAAAUUCAGUGGUAAUUCAGUAGUACCUGGCCCUUUACGAAUGAAGGUGAGUGAGAUAGCAAAUGUGAGGCUUUUGGUUUGGAUGUCUGGAUAGAUGGUUCAGGUCAUUAACUGAGAUUGGGAAGGCAGGCGAAACCAGUAUGGAUGAUUGAAUUUGGGGUGUCUUACUGGCUGCGUCAGGAGAUGUUCCGUCAGAUAGCCACAAGUAAAGGCUGGAACUUGUGGAAGGAAGAGCCCGAGAUAGGAGUUACUGCAUACAGGCAGGAGCCAAAGCCAUGAGAACGGGUGAGUCUCACUAGGAGAGAGCUAAGAUGGAUAAGGACACAACUCUGAAGGGCAUCAUUAUUUAAGGAGGAGGCAGAGAAAGAAGAGGUAGCAAAAGAAACUAAGAAACAGCAAUCAGGUGGGAGGAAAACCAAAUGAGAGUAGUCUGCUGGAAGUUAAGGGGUGAUCUGGCAAAAGGGGUGCUUCCAAAGGAUUCAGAUGCUACAGGGAUGGAGGUGUGGUGAGAACACAAAGUAGGCCUAUGGGUUUGUGAUUAGUAGAUCAGUGCAACUAUAGUGAGAGCAUUUUACUUAGAUGUUGGAGGCAGAGGACAGAUUUCAUGGUUUGAGGAUACAGAGAUGGUCAGUAUAACACCUUUUUGAGGAAGUUGGUGCUGAAAAUAAUAUGGGAGGUAGGAUUGAAAGAAUAUCUUUAAAAAUUUUUUUUCAUUGUGGUCCUUGUGGAACAUGAACAUCUUUUUAAAAUAGGAAGUUUGUGAGCAUUUGUAUAGACUGAGAGGAAAAGGAGAUGGUGGAGAUAGGGGAUGGGUAAUAAAUGGAGGCAGAUCUGGGGGACCAGCCAAGUUGGAAACAUGAGGUGAGAGCAGUGGUUCCCAACUCCAGCCACACAAUAGAAUCUUGCGGAGGUUGUCUGAACAUAACACUGCCCAAGCCUUAGCCCCAGAGAUUAUAGUUCAGUUGGUCUGGAGUGGGGUCUGGGUACCUAGAAUGGAAAAGCUCCCCAGGUGAAUUUAAUCUACAGUCAGGGCUCACUAGGUCAGAGAUAGCACGAUUAGGGAUAAGUAUACUCAGCAGCCUGGGAGUAGGAACAGGGCAAAUGGCUGCUUGAUUGAUCCAAGCUGGCGGGAAUUGGCUGGCAAGCAGUGGAAAGAUGUUAGCAAGAGUGCUGGUAAGAGCACUGUUGACAGGUUGCUCAGAUUCACCAGCACUGCAUAGGGGGCAUGAGCAAGAGAGAAGCUUCUGGGUUUCCCUGAGCUUCUGGCUUGUACUGGAUUGACUUAGUUAAGGAAUUCAGGAAGAACAUGUGAUUGGAAGAAAAUAGUAUUUUACAGUAGGAAAGAACAUGGCCCUUAUAUUAGACCCAGCUUCUGAGCCCUGCCCUACUAGUGUUAGCUCUGUGGGAAAGUUACUUCACCUCUCUGAACCUGUUUUACUAUCUGUGAAAAUACUAGUACCUAUUUAUAGGAUUGUUAUGAGGAUUAAAUAAGUUAAUGUUUGUAUAGUCCCUCACACAUAGUGUGCAAUUAAUGGUUAUGAGUUGAUUUUGAGACUUGUUGGAUUUGAGGUAUCUGUUGAAGCUCUGGGGUAGAUAUUCACACAAGUAUUUGCAGAUAUAGACUGGUCACUCAGGAGAGAUGUGGGGAAAGGAGAUAAAGAUCUGAGGGUUAUUGAUAUAUAGACCGAAAUUGAAACUGUAAGCAUGAAUUAGGUAACUGGGAGAAGAUAAUGGGCAACGGACCACACAUCCUUUAUGGCAAAAGUUUUUUUUUGUUUGUUUGUUUCUGGAAUUGAUAAUGCCCCAUUGUUAAUCCCACUGUGCAGCAAGCUUUUAGAAAGUCUGUGGCAGUACUUCUCAGAUUUUAUGUCAUGCAUGCCUGGAAAAUGAUACCAUUUAUAGGGCACCUUGGGAUAAACAGAGAAGGCUGCUUGUAUUGGAAGCAACUGGUCCAGGGCCUCUAGGAUGCCCAGGUCCCACCCAGCCACACUGCAUGAUGAGGGGAUCAAUAUCUUGGUCACACCUGUAAACCAGUGUGACUCACUGAUUUAGAAGGUUCUAAUUGUAAAACUCACAUGGAGCUCAAGGGGCAGGCUACUAAAAAUUAAGGCUAAGGCAUAGAACAGACUUGGUACUACCCAGAUGUGAGUUCACAUGUGGCCUAUCUUGGACAGGAAUUGACAAUCAGCAAACAGAUUCUGGGCAUGGAGUAAUAUAAGUUCAUAGCAGCCAUACUACAGUGUAAGAUCUUUUUGUUGUCAUCAUAAUUGUUUUGGCUAUGUUGUGAUGCUGUCCAACAAUUUACAUUAACAAAGCAUUGUGGUUUGUCUUUCAAGUAAACUAGUCACAAACCCAGCAGUCUUAGCUGGAAAAAGGUGGACAGCAGGAAUGUAGCCAUACCAAAUCCCCAUUUGUCUCAUCCUCCAGUUAGAUGGAGAGUAUGGGUCUUCUUGCUGGAGGAAUGGGUUCUUUUGUUAGCUGGGGCAGCUUAGGGCAUUUUAAAAAGAACAGACUUUGUAGUCAGACAUAACAGGGUUGGGAUCUGGCUCUGCCAUAAUCAACUGUGUGACCUUGGGCAAGUUACUUAACCCCUCUUACAAAGCCCCAGUGUUGUUCUCUGUAAAAUGGAGAUGACCCUGAUAACACCUUUCUCACUGGCUUGUAGUAACAGAAUGCAUGUAACACUUAGCACAGUGUCUGUCACAAACAGAAGGUACUUAGUAAAUGUUAGCUGUUGCUGCAGGUAUGGACCGCUUCAGCUCAUUAGUACUGUUGCAUGUCUCUGCAGCACCAAAAUGGUAUUUUUUGUU